AUGCCUUGGCGUUUCCUUUGGCGGAUUUUCUGUUUUCGGAAGUUGCUGGGUUCGUUUUAUUCAGCGGCAGUGGUGCUUUCCCGAAUCUCAGAAUGCCGUAGGUAUCUCCUCCCCAGUGUUAAAAGAUCACUGAAGUUGGAUGGUCUGUUAGAAGAAAAUUCAUUUGAUCCUUCAAAAAUCACAAGGAAGAAAAGUGUUAUAACUUAUUCUCCAACAACUGGAACUUGUCAAAUGAGUCUAUUUGCUUCUCCCACAAGUUCUGAAGAGCAAAAGCACAGAAAUGGACUAUCAAAUGAAAAGAGAAAAAAAUUGAAUCACCCCAGUUUAACUGAAAGCAAAGAAUCUACAACAAAAGACAAUGAUGAAUUCAUGAUGUUGCUAUCAAAAGUUGAGAAAUUGUCAGAAGAAAUCAUGGAGAUAAUGCAAAAUUUAAGUAGUAUACAGGCUUUGGAGGGCAGUAGAGAGCUUGAAAAUCUCAUUGGAAUCUCCUGUGCAUCACAUUUCUUAAAAAGAGAAAUGCAGAAAACCAAAGAACUAAUGACAAAAGUGAAUAAACAAAAACUGUUUGAAAAGAGUACAGGACUUCCUCACAAAGGCAUUAAGGCUGACUUGCCCAUUACCAGAUUUUCCCAAAGGACCGAGUUCCUGCAUAGAGGAGACUGUUAUCACUAAACCAUGUUUGUAAAUUUCUAAUAAUCAUUGAUUUAAAUGAAAACUCAGUUUAAAAAAUAUAUAAUACAUAGUAUCUAUAUAAGUAUGUUAUAUACUACUGUGUGUUAUAUUCUAUUCUACGUAGUCAUUGUCCAAUUCUGUUUCUUGGCAGGAGCUACAUUAGCUCUUUAUAUUUCCUGAGGUAUUAAAAACUUCAUUAGCUUUUUAACUAAUUUUGGGAAAUUCAUAUUGCCUAAAAAAUAGAUUAAAGCUUAUUUUUGUUGUAAUUUGAUUUUGAGCUAUAUAGUUUUCCUGAGUGCUUUUCCUACCUCUUUCUCUGGUUCCUAACAUACAUAUUAGUUUUGGGGGUUUUUUGUUUGUUUUGUUUUUUGGUUAAUGAUUAUGUACACACAAAUGUGCACACACAUGCAAAUUUUUUGUACUAAGCUAACAACUUUUACCCUUUUCUGCUCAUAUUCAUUUUAAGAGGAUUUUGCUAAUUCUUUUGACAUCUCAAACUAGUUUGCUUUAUAUGUCCCUCAUUUUGCAAUCUGGCCUUGAAAUUUCCACUUUCUUUUAUUUAUUUAUUUUUAUUAUGCUAUUACACAGAAUUGUUUAAAUUUUAAAAUGUUUUGGGAGUUUGUCAUAAUAUUAGAAAAUAAGUAAAAUAAAAAUCAUCCCUAUAAUAUGUAUAGGAUUUGUUAAGGUAAUUAUGAAAAUUAGAAUAAGCCAAUUACUUGUUUCACUAUCAAAAGAAUGUCCUUCAGAUUCUUCUGGGUUUUUGGUGGGUUUUUUUGUUUGUUUGUUUUUUGGUCUUUCAGAUUCUUAAAAAAUUUUCCUGGAAUAGUUAAAAUAGACAAUACCAUGAGAAUUUCAAUAUUUAUGCUAUCAUUGCCUCUUCUAAUUGGUCUUUUAGUUCUAGUAAUAUUUAUUUUUUCAUUUCAGUGGGAAUUUCAGUUAAUGUCAGUUACAGUCUUUAUUACAGGAAGAGUAGAAUUAUAAAAAUAACACUCUAGUGUUUUAAAUAAAUAGACAUCUGACACACAUUCUUAAGGCUUUAUAUAACUUAUUCAAGAGAAAUUUAAAACAUACACAAUAAAAUUAAAAGGCACACUGAGAUUUUCAUAGUGUCAUAAGAACUGGACCUGGUAAAUCAGGGGAUGCCUUGAUGAGAGUAUAUGAAUAAAAGAGGAUCUCCUCUGCUAAACACAGAUUUCUUAAACAAAGGAAGGCUUCUUUCUUUCUUCAGUUACUUAGGAAAUAAGCCUAAUUUUGCUUUCUUCAAUAACACUGGCUUUAUGACUAUUAGGAAAAUAAUGAAAUGAAAGGUUCUUUUUCUGUAAGAUUUGGAUGUGAAUUUUCAUAAUUAUUUUAAAUUUGUUAUGCUGAAGACUUAAGACAUAUGACCAUUCAGUGGGCUGAUACAGAUGAAAUGUCACAUUAUCAUCACAUGGUGAGGCAUGAAAUUUAUUUACUUUACAUAAUCAACCUCUACUUAAAACAACUUGUUACAGAUAUUCCUUAGUCAAUAGAUGGCAUUAUAUAGUAGUUAAUAUUUUCAGUUUUUUCUGAAGAUAAUUAAAAAUACCAUCGUUAGUCUAUGACUAGUACUUCCAAUAAACAAAAUGUUUUUGAAAAGAAUGUAAGCAAAUUGUAGAGCAGUUGCCAAGAUAUGAAAUCUAGACACUUAGCUUCAGUCCAAAACAUAUUUUAUCUGUUUUGAGAAUAAUUGUGUAGGUUGCAGUAUGCAUAUUUUAAAUGAAAUGGAACCAUCUGAACUUUACAUUGUUCAGUGUUUCAGCUGUUUGUAAUAGAAAAUAUUUCAGAAUUUCCAACUUUGGUCUGUUUUAAAAAGCAUAAACUACAAUGUUCCUGUAUUCUUUAGUUAACUUUCUGUAUUCUUACAUAGUAAAAUUCGUCUUGGUUAUAGAUUUUAAAGUUAUCAGAUUCUUAGACAACAGGACAAAUUUAAAACUCUUUCUGUUCUAACACUAUAAAAUAGUUUGAUAUUGCCUCUUCAUUCUAACCACCCACUGAAGUAUUUUUUAAACAUAAAAAUAUGUUGUUCUUUCCCCAACUCAGGCUUGAAAAAGUAUUCAUCAUAUCAGCUGAAUAAUUUCACUCCCAGAAGACUACUACCCUUUUAGUUUUCUAUUUUAUCUUAACAUUAAACAAUAUAUUUUUUUCAAACAGAUACUUCAAUUUUAAAAGCACUGAGGUUUGAAGUUUAGACGUGACGACUUUUAGGAGAAACAACAGAAAUUCCCCCUAUGCUUUAACAUUCUGGGUUUAUCUGGAGAUAAAAAAUGAAGCCAUUAAUUUUGAUAGCACAAAUAUACAUUAAUGUACAACUAUAGUCCUCAGCUCUUUAUAAUGAUUCAGCUAUCAUGUAUGCCAUAUGUGAAUCAUAACCUUUCCUAUUAAUAAUGUUAAUGCUCUUGUUUUACACGAUUCGUCAUUGUUUUGGGGUAUGCAUUUCAGCUGCUAAAAAUGCUUACUUGAGAUUUGUCUAGGAUUUAAGUAAAAAUAAACUGAUUUAUUACUUUUCAAA